CCGAAACUGGCCCGAGGGAGGGCCCCUGGGUCUGGGAAGAGUUGGAGGGAGGAGCUCAUCAGUUGAACCGUCCUUGACCUGGUGUCUGUUUGGAAAGGGAUGCGGCCUAAGUUUAAGCUCCCUCCCAGCCAAGUGAGCGGCUCCUCAACAUCGCAGGGCUUUGCACACUCACCUACACUUGCAGCAGGCGGGAAAGGGAAGGAAGCCACCGUCCACUGCCCCUUAUUCUCCUGGCACACUUGGCUGAUUAAGGCAGUGUUCAAGCUCAGGUCGAGGCUGCAGCUGAUUCACCACAACAUGGCAAAUCUUUUUAUAAGGAAAAUGGUGAACCCUCUGCUCUAUCUCAGUCGUCACACGGUGAAGCCUCGAGCCCUCUCCACAUUUCUAUUUGGAUCCAUUCGAGGUGCAGCCCCCGUGGCUGUGGAACCCGGGGCAGCAGUGCGCUCACUUCUCUCACCCGGCCUCCUGCCCCAUCUGCUGCCUGCGCUGGGGUUCAAAAACAAGACUGUCCUUAAGAAGCGCUGCAAGGACUGUUACCUGGUGAAGAGGCGGGGUCGGUGGUACGUCUACUGUAAAACCCAUCCGAGGCACAAGCAGAGACAGAUGUAGACCCUUUCCCUCCAGAGUCACGCACAUACUCGUCAUCGCAUCACUUGGGAGAAUGGUUGUAUCUUAUGGAAGGAAUUAUCACAUCAAGGAGUCAGGGGAAAGUGACUGGAAGCAAACGCCCUAAAAGUUACCCAUCACGUUUCAGUGUAAAUGAGUAACUAUAGAAGACAUUGCGUUAUCUUAUUUCCAAAACGUUCCAACUAAAAAACAUUUUCCUAUUAAAAUAGACCUUCCGAAUA